AGGCUGCCCGCUGGCCUCGGAGCAGGCGCCUGCGCCCUCGGCCUCGGCCUAGUCAUGCUCCGUCCCGGCGCGCAGCUGCUGCGGGGCCUCCUGCUGCGGAGCUGCCCGCUGCAGGGCUCCCCCGGGCGCCCGCGCUCUGUCUGCGGCCGGGAAGGAGAGGAAAAACCACCCUUAUCUGCAGAAACACAAUGGAAAGACAGAGCAGAAACAGUGAUAAUUGGAGGUGGCUGUGUUGGUGUGAGUCUGGCUUAUCACCUGGCCAAAGCAGGGAUGAAAGAUGUGGUCCUGCUGGAGAAAUCAGAGCUCACGGCUGGAUCUACCUGGCACGCAGCAGGUUUAACAACUUACUUUCAUCCUGGAAUAAACUUGAAGAAAAUACAUUAUGAUAGCAUCAAACUUUAUGAGAAACUGGAAGAAGAAACUGGUCAGGUGGUGGGAUUCCAUCAGCCAGGUAGUAUCAGACUUGCUACCACCCCUGUAAGGGUAGAUGAAUUUAAAUAUCAAAUGACUCGGACUGGCUGGCAUGCAACAGAACAGUAUCUCAUUGAACCUGAAAAAAUUCAAGAGAUGUUCCCUUUACUCAACAUGAAUAAGGUUUUAGCUGGAUUGUAUAAUCCUGGAGAUGGUCACAUUGAUCCUUAUUCUCUAACUAUGGCACUGGCUGCUGGGGCUAGGAAAUGUGGUGCCCUUUUAAAAUAUCCUGCACCAGUAACUUCUCUGAAAGCCAGGUCAGAUGGAACAUGGGACGUUGAAACACCACAGGGGUCUAUGAGAGCAAAUAGAAUUGUGAAUGCUGCAGGAUUUUGGGCUCGUGAAGUAGGUAAAAUGAUUGGACUAGAACAUCCUCUCAUUCCGGUUCAACAUCAAUAUGUUGUUACAUCGACUAUAUCUGAAGUGAAAGCUUUGAAACGAGAACUGCCUGUGCUCCGUGACCUGGAAGGAUCAUAUUAUCUCCGACAGGAAAGGGAUGGGCUUUUGUUUGGUCCAUAUGAAAGUCAAGAGAAAAUGAAAGUUCAGGACUCCUGGGUCACCAAUGGAGUUCCUCCAGGUUUUGGAAAGGAACUCUUUGAGUCUGAUCUAGAUCGAAUCAUGGAACACAUCAAAGCUGCCAUGGAAAUGGUUCCUGUCUUGAAAAAGGCUGACAUCAUCAAUGUUGUCAAUGGUCCUAUCACGUAUUCUCCUGACAUUCUGCCUAUGGUGGGGCCCCAUCAGGGGGUCAGAAACUACUGGGUGGCUAUAGGCUUUGGAUAUGGCAUAAUCCACGCUGGUGGGGUAGGGAAAUAUCUCAGUGACUGGAUCCUGCAUGGAGAACCUCCUUUUGAUCUGAUAGAAUUGGAUCCUAAUCGCUAUGGCAAAUGGACAACAACCCAGUACACUGAGGCCAAAGCAAGAGAAUCAUAUGGAUUCAACAAUAUUGUUGGUUAUCCUAAAGAAGAACGGUUUGCUGGGAGGCCGACUCAACGAGUCAGUGGGCUCUAUCAAAGGCUGGAGUCUAAGUGUUCCAUGGGGUUCCAUGCUGGCUGGGAGCAGCCGCACUGGUUCUACAAACCAGGCCAGGACACUCAGUACAGGCCAAGUUUUCGCCGCACAAACUGGUUUGAGCCUGUGGGCUCGGAGUAUAAACAGGUUAUGCAAAGAGUAGCGGUAACUGACCUAUCACCAUUUGGCAAGUUUAACAUCAAAGGCCAAGAUUCCAUUAGACUACUGGACCAUCUCUUUGCAAAUGUCAUUCCAAAGGUGGGUUUUACAAAUAUAAGUCACAUGUUAACACCCAAGGGUCGAGUGUAUGCUGAGCUGACUGUUUCUCACCAAUCUCCUGGGGAGUUUCUUUUAAUUACUGGCUCUGGAUCAGAACUUCAUGAUCUUAGAUGGAUUGAAGAAGAAGCAGUCAAAGGUGGAUAUGAUGUUGAAAUUAAAAACAUAACUGAUGAGCUUGGAGUUCUUGGAGUUGCUGGGCCACAGGCAAGAAAGGUCCUUCAGAAACUGACCUCUGAAGAUCUUAGUGAUGAUGUUUUCAAGUUUCUUCAAACCAAGUCCUUAAAGGUUUCCAACAUUCCUGUCACUGCUAUUAGGAUAUCUUAUACUGGUGAGCUGGGUUGGGAGCUGUAUCACAGAAGAGAAGAUUCUGUGGCGCUGUAUGACGCUAUCAUGAAUGCAGGCCAGGAGGAGGGAAUCGACAAUUUUGGAACCUAUGCCAUGAAUGCCUUACGCCUGGAGAAAGCCUUCAGAGCCUGGGGGUUAGAGAUGAACUGUGAUACAAAUCCUUUGGAAGCUGGACUGGAAUAUUUUGUGAAGUUAAAUAAGUAACUCCUGGUGACUUGGGAAAUUGCACAUUAGCUGAUCAAACAUAGUGCAUUCAUUGAUCCUUCUGGAUACUCACAGUGUGGAGCAGCCUCACUUCAGCAUAUCUGUCCAUCUGCUUAUCAAGCAUCUUUGUGGGUAACUGCAACAUCUGAAUAUAAGCAAAUAACACGUUUCAAACGUUUUCGGCAUAAAAUGGGUAUUAACUGAGAAGCUAAUAUAAGCCCAAAUAAUCAUAACCGAUAAGACACUCCAAAGGGAACUCCUACAUCAGUGGUUCUUAAAAUGUAGCCUUCAGACUAACAGCAUCAGCCUCAUUGGGAGCUUGUUUGAAAUGCUAAUUCUCAGGUCCCACCCUAGAACUACUAAAUCAGAAUCUCUGGGAGUCAGGCCAACAAAUCUGUUUUAACAACCCCUGCAGGGGAUUCUGAUGCAUCUAAGGUUUGAGAAGCAUUACUCUAAAUAAUUAUAGUGGAAAAGCAUAUCAUGAGGCCAAUUUAUUACAGCCAAGCUCAUCUGUACAAGCCUUACAAAUAUAAAUGAGGUUACUCCAUUGAGCAGUGCCUAAGAGUUAUAAUAAAACAACUUAAUAGAGCUGGGGUGAGUGGUAGUAUUGAAGAAUAAGGGCAGCAGCGGCUACUGUUUAGGAUAUUUGUUAGAACUCCAAAAAUAAAAUGUCCUGCCCUAGAUGGUUGUAAACUAAAGACUGAUUUCCCAUCCUGUGGAAAUACGUGAAUACAUGUAUAUGACUCAAUCAGGCCAAGGAAACCUUUUUCAUGACCCUGUGUCAGUUCCCAAAUUCUGAGCUAUAAUAUUAAAAUAAAACAUGUGUAUUUAUAGUAUGAGAUUUUAGGAAAACGAACCUCCUAAAGGGUUUUAAAGGGAAUAUCUUUCUGUACAUUCUCCCCAUGGCUUUUAUUUUUAUGAUGUACCAUCUGCCUCCAGACCAGAGAAAGCAGGUGCUUGGAAUUUGGGCAGACCCUAGCAGCAGAUUGCUCCCUCUGAUAGCAGAAGCCUUACUUUAGCUGUUUCAAAUAAGGUUAAAAAUGGCCCAACUCUUGAAAGUGCUAAAUUUCUGUUAUUGGUCACCAGUAGGUAGAUAGAUAACUGAUUCUUUUGCUUCAGUGUUCGGAUAUUAUUGUUUGGGGAUAAGGCAUAGAUAAAUAAUCCCUUCGUAUUGAAAUGGGAUUUUCAAAUAUCUUUUAUGAUUAUUAGCAGGGGUGGAUUGUGUCUUUGUUAGUUAAGUUAUACAGCCAAAUAACCAAAGCUCAUCUCAGAACGUAGUUAGUUGUUUAGAAGAUACUAAUUUUGAUUUCUGGCAUGUUUUUAUAAUUUCUGAAUUGUUGUUUCUCAUUCAAGUGUCACAAAGUUAAUUCCUAAUGAUUUUAUAGGGUAAAGGUCCUUGUAGCCCAAGGACCUGGCCCCCAACUGAGCCAGUCUUUUUCAAUUAUGUCAAUUCAAGUGGCUAGUUGGUAUUAACCUACUCAUAAUGAUGCUUGCUAAUCUCCAAGACAGGUGAAUAGAUUAGAUCAACUUUGGUGGUUUUGUAGCAGUCUAUAAUGUGAAACGGAUGCCUGGAAACCUUAUUAACAUUACAAACUAAGCUUUGUAACUUGACCAUUCAAGUCCUGUGCCUAAAAACCAAAAUGUUACCCAAACUAGCUUCAUACAACAUUUUAAAUACUGUAAGCCUAUAAUUGCUUCGGAAAAUCGAUGCUAUAGGAGAACAGAAGCAACAGCUAAUACAGAGAGAUAUUUAUAUUUGAUACCAAAACAAACACAGCAAAAACCCUGGCAUUUUACAAUUGUUUGAAAUCAGUUAUUUCUUUCCCUUCAGAGCAAACAUUUAGAAUUCUCUGGUUGGCCCUUAGGCAUUUACACUAUGAUCGUUUAAGCCAUAAUGUGAAGAAAAGGUAGAAGCUGACUGUAUCAGAGCUAGAUGGGUCCCUGGGGAUCAGCUGGUACUCCCCUCCCCCAUCUGAAGCAGAGGAAACUGAAGCACAGAGAGGGAAAGUGACCUGGGGGAGGCCACUGCUUUAGCUUAGGUCGAACGCCACCCUCUGACCUCAUCGUGGAGCUUUCCCACCCACCACUUUCCCCCACAAAGUCCUUUUCCACAGUGGGCUUAUCAGACUUGAAAGACUGCCCAAGAAUUUCUCUCUCUGGUAACAUAUAUUGUUUGUAUGGACUACCUUUUAUUAAUAGACACUUCCCCCACAUGUUUUUGCUGUAACUAAUUUUGUGUUUUAUGAUAGGAUCAGAAUAGCUGCUUUGCCCAUUUUAAGGAGGAAAAUGGCUGGGUGAGCAGAUGGGCCAUCAGGCCUUAUUAGGGUGAAUCGUGUUCUUGUCAAAACCUGUCAGCAAGUAGGGAAAAGAACAAUGGAGUACUGAAGAACUCUUUCAUCACAAAGGGAGACGGCGCAGUGGCCCUUGCUUCCUUCCGUCUUGGAGUUGUUCCAGCCUCCUUCCCCUGCUGUUGGCUUAUGUGAAGUUGAUACACAUGUAUCAUUCAUUCAUCCGUUCAUCUAGUAGACAUUUAUUAAGUACCGCUGAUUAGACACCUUGCUAACCCAUAGAUCUAAAUGUUAAAGAUAUACUCCUGAUGGCUCUCAGAUCUCAUGAACCUGGAAACAAAUAAUAUUUCAGGAACUAAAGCUGUAGGGAUACGUUCUUAGCCGUAAUUGUGAAGAUAACCCUUCCGCAAGUGGAGGGCUCUCCAGCCGCAUACAACACUGCCAUCUUGUGGGAAGUGCUCCGUAGAGCCACUUCAGGAAGCCUUGACCAAAGCUGCGGUAAAAAUAAUUGAAUCUGUACUUUUAAAAUCUUCUUAACUAAAAACGCUUCACCUGAAACGACUCAUAUCAUUGUUCUCAAUGGUAUUUUUGGUAUGUUCCAAAGGAAGUAACUUUUGGGAGGAAAAUCAGUAGCCUUUGUUUAGUUGGAGAUGGAAGAAAUGCAUUAAUCAAGAGCAAAAGGAAAAUCAGCUGCCUUUGGAUGGAGUCAUAGGCAUUCCUGGAAUUUUCAUGGUGGAAAUAUUGAAUUUUUGUCCAUUUCUGGAGAACCUCCACGAAGAUUCACAGAGACUCAAGUAUUAAACGUAAUGUGUUGAAGCACAUCAGAAGAAUUUGUUUUCUAUAAUAUGUUUCUCCCUCUUUUUCUCACUCUCUCCUUCUCCCUCUCUUUCCCUUUUUCUCUCUCCUUCCCCUCUCUCCCCGUGUAGAGCUUCUAACUAGUAGAAACAGAAUAAAAUGUAAUCUCUAUUAAACAUAAGUUAUAAGACAAUGUUGAUUCUAGAAAAUGCAGGGUCUCUUUUGGAAGAAAUAUUUAAAGCAUAACUGUUCGAUAACCAAAAACAAAACAACCCAAAAAAGCUGGUAAAGAGGCAAAGCGCUUAGUACCAAGCCUUCCACACCCCAGGUGUUCAGUAAAUAUUAGCUAUUAUUAAAACAUCAGAGUGCUAAAAACAAAAAAAUCCAAGUGGAAUCAAACCAUUGUUCACAGACAACAAGCUAGAAAGAAAUUGUUAAUAUAGUGGUCAAAGCAUCCAAUUCUCUUUGGGAAAUUUGAGGUAAAUGGUAAUAAGAAUUGAGGAGGCAGAAAAUUUUCAGUGAUACUUAGCCCUGGCUGGACAUUAGAAUCAUCUGGGGUAUGAUUCUUUUAAAUAAUAUUUCGCUGUUUAAAAUCCCAAGGCCCAGGCUACACCCAAGAUCAAUUUAAAAAGAAGCUCUUGUAGGGACUCAGGCAUCAGUUGUUUUUAAUUCCCCAGGUGAUUCUGCAGAGAUGGAGAAUUACUGUCUUCAACCAAAGAUUUUCAACUGGCUGAACAUAUUAUCCUGAAGAACUAAAAAUUACCUGAACUGAAAGAACUAAAAACUACUCAAGUAGUUCUCAAGGUGUGGUCCACAGACCAGCAGCAUCACUGUCACCUGGGACCUGCUAGAAAAUUCAAAUUGUUGAGUACCAUCCCAGACCCCCAAAAUCAGAAGCUGCCAGGGUGGAGCCCAACUAUCUAUCUAUCUAUCGAUCUAUCUGUCUAUCUAACUAUUUUUAUUGAGACGGAGUCUUGCCCUAUUGCCCAGGCUGGAGUGCAGUGGUGCAAUUUUGGCUCACUACAACCUUCGCCUCCCAGGUUCAAGCAAUUUUCUUGCCUCAGCCUCCCCAGUAGCUGGUAUUACAAGCACCCGCCACCAUGCCCAGUUGAUUUUUGUAUUUUUAGUAGAGACGAGGUUUCACCUUGUUGGCCAGGUUGGUCUUGAACUCCUGACCUCAGGUGAUCCACCUGCCUCAGCCUCUCAAAGUGCUAGGAUUACAGGCAUGAGUCACCGCACUUGGCCCAACAAUCUAUUCUAAUAAGCCCUCCAGGUAGUUUCAAUGCAGUUUAUUUAAGUACAUGGACCUACCCCAAAUCAAUUAGAUUUUCUCUAGGUGUAAGGUCCAUGGUUCCUUUUUAAAGCUCCACAGGUGAUUUUUUUUUUUUAAUGCAGUGAAUAUUGAGAACCACUGUUUUAGUUCUUAUAACUUCAUACCAACUUCAGUCUUGAAAGUACAUAGGAAAGUAGAAAAACAUGUGGAUUGGUCAGAGGAUGGUGCUAUAGAACUGUGGUGGAAAGGAUGUAAAUUAAUAGAUCUAGAGCCUAUUCCAGCUAGGCUACAGGUUCGUAUUCUGCCCCAUAUCUUUGUUUUUUCUUUUAGAACUGGGUAGUAAGUGAAUUUUUUUUAAGUCACCAAAUUCUAACUGCGUGGCCCAGGAAAGCCAUUUAACUUGAUUUUCAUGCUGAGAUUUUUAAUCUGUAAAAGAAGGCUACUUUUGCAAGUCUAAAAUCCUAUGGAAUGCCUCCAACACAGUGGUUGAAGACAUUGGUGCCAUGUUAUCUUUAUGAGCCACAUAAUUGUGUCAUCUGAAUUAAGCUAUCCUUAUUCUGUUACCCAUUUUCAUUGCUGAGUGAUAAGGGGAAGGAGAGGAGAAAGGAGGGGAGGGGAAGAGAAGGAAAGGAAGAGGAAAGAAGUAAAACCUAGCUGAAGUGUAGUUGACCAUUCCUGAAACACCUGUCAGGAUACAUUAAACUAAAGCCAUUGAAUCAUUAUUUUCAUAUAUAUCCAAUUUCUGUUAUGAAACAGUACUUUGUUUCUACCCUAAGAGCUGAAAUGUGAAGUUUAGCUGACUGCUUUCAAAUUUGGAUAUCCAUGGAAACCCAGGUCUAGGAAUGAAUUGAAAUAAUUUUUAAGAUUGCUUUUAUUUUUAUUAUUAUUUUAAGUGUAUUUGAACAUGCAAUAAUUGACAUAUUUAAAGUAAGCAAUUUGAUAAGUUUUAGUACAUGAUACAGCAGUGAAACCAUCACCGCAGUGAAGAUAGUAAACCUAUCCCUCAUCCCCGGGGUGUCCAUGCCCCUUUGUGAUCCCUACCCGCCACCCUCCCCACAGCCUCACCUACCCCCCAGGCAACAAUUUAUGUCUGAGACUAUAGGUUAUUUUGCAAUUUUUAAAAUAAAUGCAAAAUCUAUAAAAAUGGAAUCAUAGAGUAUAUACUUUUUUUGUGUGUUAAUUCUUUCCCUCGGCAUAACUUGAGAGUCAUUUGUGUUGUUAUGUUUAUUAAUAGAUCAUUCCCAGUGGCAUCUCAUACCUGUAAUCCCAGCACUUUGGGAGGUGGAGGUGGAAGGGUUGCCUCAACCCAGGUUUGAAACCAGACUGGGCAACAUAGUGAGACUUCCAUCUCCACAAAAAAUUAGCCGGGCAUGGUGACACAUGCCUGUAGUCCUAGCUACUUGAGAGGCUGAGGAAGGAGGACUGCUUGAGCCUGGGAGGUCAAGGCUGCAGUGAGUCAUGUUUGUGCCACUGCACUCCAGCCAGGGCAACUGAGCAAGGCUCUGCCUCAAAAAAAUAAUAAUAAUUCCCUUUUAUAGCAGGUAGUAUUCCAUUGUAUGGAUAUACUACAAUUUGUUUGUGUACUCACUCAUUGAUAAAUAUUUGGGAUGUUUCCAGUUUAGGGCUAUUACAAAUAAAACUCCAGUAGUCUCUUGGUAUACCUGGAGGAUUGGUUCUAUGACUGCCCAAGGGUACCAAAAUUUGCUUGAAGUCCGGCAGUUUGUCUGUGGAAACUGCCUAUAGAAAAAGUUGGGUUUUGCAUCCUGCAAAUACUGUCUUUUUGAUCUGCUUGGUUGAAAAAAAUGCACAUAUAAGUGGAUCCGUGCAGUUCAAACCUGAGUUGUUCAACAGUCAGCUGACACUGUGAACAUUUGUGUACAAGUAUUUGUAUGAACAUAGGCUUUCUUUUCCCUAGGUAAAUACCUAGGAGUGAAAUGACUGAAUAAAAUGAAAGUGUAUGGUAACUUUGUAAGAAACCGUUUUGCCAAGCUGUGUGCCAUUUUAUAUAUUAUAGUCCUACCAGCAGUAUGUGAAGUUCCAGCUCCUCUACAUCCUUGUCAAAUACUUUUCAUGGUCAGUCUUUUUAACUUUAGCUAUUCUAAGAGAUAUGUAGUGAUGUCUCAUGAUGGUUUUAAUUUAUUUCCUUAAUGUCAAAUGAUGUUGGACAUUUUUUGAUGUGCCUCCCUGCCAUUUCUAUAUCUUUUUUUGUGAAAUGUCUGGUUAAAUCUCUUACCUAGGGUUUGUUUUUUUUAAUUGAGUUUUUAAAGUGCUUUCUGUAUUCUUUAUCAGAUACAUGCUUUGCAAAUUUUUUUCAGAUGUCUUGACUUUUCAUUUGUCUCAUGGUGUCUUUCAAAGAGCCAUUUUUAAUUUUUGAAUUUUAAAGUUCUUAUCAAUUGUUCUUUUAUGAAUCAUGCUUUUGGUUCAUAUCUAGGAAAUCUUUGCCUAAUCCAAAGUCAUAAAGAUUUUCUGCUAUGUUUUCUUCUAGAAGUUUUAUUAUUUUACUUUUUACAUUUAGGUCUAUGAUCCAUUUUUAGUUGAUCUUGUAUCUGGUAUGAGGUAUGGACUGAAGUUUUAUUUAUUUGUACUUGGAUAACCAAUUGCUUUCAGCACCAUUUGUUGAAAAGACUAUAUAUUCUGAAUUUCAUUGCCUUUAUAUCUUCGUCAGUAUGUUUAUAUCUUUGUCCAUUUGUUUGUAGGUCUAUUUCUGGACUCUGUUGUAUUCUGUAUAUCUGUUUAUCUUUCCAAAUGCCAAUACUACAGUGUCUUGAUUACUGUUGCUCAAAUAAGGUUGUGAUAGCCCUGCAACUUUGUUCUCUUUUUUAAAGCUGUUUUGGCUAUUCUAGGUCCUUUGAAUUUCAUUAAUUUUAGAAUCAGCUUGUCAAUGUGUACCAAAAAACCUGCUAGACUUUAUUGGAAUUGCAUUUUAUCUACAGGUCAAUUCAAGUAUUACAAUUCAUGAACAAGUUCCAUCUCUCCAUUUAUUCAGGUCAUCUUUUAUUUCUGUCAGGAAUCUUUUAUAGUUUUCAGUAUACAGGUCUUACAUAUCUUUUAACAUAUUUAUCCUUAAGUAUUUCAUGUUUUGAUACUGUUGUAGAUGGUAUUUUUAAUUUCAAUUUUCAGUUGUUUAUUGCCAAAUUAUAGAAAUACAAUUGGUCUUAUAUGUUGAUCUUAUAUUUUGGAACUUUGCUCAAUCUGCUUAGUGGUUCUAGUAGCAUUUUUGUAGAUUCCAUCAGAUUGUCACAUGGACAAUCAUGUUGUAUAAAAAUAAAGCUUUUCUUUGUCUUUUCUAA